GGUGUGUGCGGAACAUGGCGGAGCGCGGCAGGAAGCGGCCGUGCGGCCCGGGUGAACACGGCCAAAGGAUUGAGUGGCGAAAAUGGAAGCAACAGAAGAAAGAGGAGAAAAAAAAAUGGAAGGAUCUCAAGCUGAUGAAAAAACUGGAGCGGCAGCGGGCACAGGAGGAACAGGCAAAGCGCCUGGAAGAGGAGGAGGCAGCGGCAGAGAAGGAGGACCGCGGGCGGCCCUACACACUGAGCGUAGCCCUGCCGGGCUCCAUCCUGGACAAUGCUCAGUCGCCGGAGCUUCGCACCUACUUGGCCGGUCAGAUUGCCAGAGCCUGUGCCAUCUUCUGUGUGGAUGAGAUCGUGGUGUUUGAUGAGGAGGGCCAGGAUGCCAAGACUGUGGAGGGGGAAUUCACAGGAGUUGGGAAGAAGGGGCAGGCGUGCGUACAGCUGGCCCGGAUCCUGCAGUACCUGGAGUGUCCACAGUACCUGAGGAAGGCGUUCUUCCCCAAGCACCAGGAUCUACAGUUUGCAGGGCUCCUGAACCCCCUGGACAGCCCCCACCACAUGCGUCAGGAUGAGGAAUCCGAGUUCCGAGAGGGCAUCGUGGUGGAUCGGCCCACCCGGCCAGGCCACGGCUCCUUUGUCAACUGUGGCAUGAAAAAGGAGGUGAAGAUUGACAAGAACCUGGAGCCCGGGCUUCGGGUGACUGUGCGACUGAACCAGCAGCAGCACCCAGACUGCAAGACCUACCAUGGCAAAGUGGUAUCAUCGCAGGACCCUCGCACCAAAGCUGGUCUCUACUGGGGCUACACCGUCCGACUGGCUUCCUGCCUCAGUGCUGUGUUUGCUGAGGCCCCCUUCCAAGAUGGGUAUGACCUGACCAUCGGGACGUCAGAGCGCGGCUCAGAUGUGGCCUCUGCCCAGCUUCCCAACUUCAGGCAUGCUCUUGUGGUGUUCGGGGGCCUCCAGGGUCUGGAAGCUGGAGCGGAUGCUGACCCCAACCUGGAGGUGGCUGAACCCAGUGUCCUCUUUGACCUGUACGUCAAUACCUGUCCUGGCCAGGGUAGCCGUACCAUCCGCACGGAGGAAGCCAUCCUCAUCUCCCUGGCCGCCCUGCAGCCUGGCCUCAUCCAGGCGGGUGCCCGGCACACCUGAAAGUUCUAAGGGGCCGAGGACAUCAGUGAAGCAGCAGUGAAACCAGGGGCUCUGCAGGUCACUUGGGACGGACGCCACCAGACUUGUCUCCAAAAAUCACCACCUUUAAUACUCCCCGGCCUGCACACACCCACAGUCUCACUGGGCUCCACCCUCACUUACUGCCCGCCGUGAUGGCCUUGAGGCUGCCUGCCCGCGCCAGGAUGUUUGGCACAAAGAGCAGCCCCGAAGCCCGCUCAAUGCUCUCGAUGGGCACCAGGAAGCGCUCCAGUGGGAUGGCCUCAUCCACAGGUGCGUUGGGCAUCACGUAGGUGCGGAGCUCAAUUUGCCCACCUGCUGCCUCCAGGAUCAGCACCUUGAAGAAGUGUGUGGGCACUGCCACGUGGUUCUUGCCGAUGACCUGGUACUUUACGUAGGAUUUCCCAUCAGCCUCUGUCCUGUGGGCAGACCCAGGCACACGUGGGCAGGGGGCCUGGAUGAACCCAAAGCCACCUCUUCCAGGCAGCCUUCCCUGAUCUGUCCUCUAACUUCUGUCAACCUGCAGGACCACGCCCUCACUGUGAGACUUCUGUAGCCUGCCUGGCUCCUCCUUGAGGCUGGAACUCUCUCCAGGGUGGUUAACUCUUUCCCUCUGUUUUCCUUAUGCCCAACACUGGGUCAGGCAGAGUGGGCGACAAUAAACGCUGCUAGGAGAAUCGAGCCUUCUGAAUAUUCACAUUCGUCUGAGGGGAGACUUAACGACUGUCCAUCUCUCCCCACAGAGGUGAGCAACAAGUGGGCAAGGACCAUGACAGGUGAUAUCCCAGCACCAGCACAGGUGCCAGGACACCGGACGGGGGCUCCCCCUCAGCAGAGUCUCCUCCCUUCCACCAGGCCCUAGGAGGCACCUGCUAAUGAAAUUUGAUCAGUGCCCCAACCACCGCCUUGGCCAGCCUAUGCCGAGCCCUUACCAUGGACCAGGCCCUGGGGAAGCAUGUGACAUCAACCAAGAGGUCACAGGUUUUGCAGAGGGGGACACAGGUCAUUUGCCCACAGCACCAAGGAACUAGGUGAUGAGGCCUGGACUCCAUCCCGAGCCUGUGGAUUCCAGAGUGAGCUGCUCAGCCUGGACCUGUUGCCUCUCAGCCCCAGCCCUCUGCAGGCCAGAAAAACCACGGAGCACACCCAGAGGUGCUCAGUUGCUUCCACCUGAGAGGCAGGGCUGCACAGGAGCAAGAGUGGAGGCCCUGGGUCAGGCAGAUCUAGAUUCAAACUCCCGAGAAGGGUGGAGGGAAGUGCUCCAAGCAGAGCAGAGACUGAAGGCGGGAGAGCCUGGUGCACCGCGGACCUGCAGGGGGAAGGCAUGAGAGCUCGGUGCACUGGGGACCUGCAUGGGGAAGGCGGGAGAGCUCGGUGCACUGGGGACCUGCAUGGGGAAGGCGUGAGAGCUCGGUGCACUGGGGACCUGCAUGGGGAAGGCGGGAGAGCUCGGUGCACCUCGGACCUGCAGAGGGAAGGUGGGAGAGCUUGGUGCACCGCAGACCUGCAGGGGGAAGGCGGGAGAGCUUGGUGCACUGCAGACCUGCGGGGGGAAGGUGGGAGAGCUUGGUGCACUGCAGACCUGCGGGGGGUUCCAUAUUGGCAGAACAAGAUUGGGUGGGCAUGCCAAGAGGUGACAGCAGGGAGAAGCGGGGGCAGAUUCAGGGCCUGCUGCUGCCCAUGGGCAGAGGAGAGAUGGUCAGGGGUACCCGACAGGUCUUUGGCUGUGGAGGUGGAAUGAGGGGACUCGAGGCAGGGAAGCUGACAGGCUUGCCAAGAAACCAGAUGAGUAGGGAACUGGUAUUGACCCAGAGCCUGGGGCAAGCCUGGCCCUGUGAGUGGCAGUAGGGGCCUCAGGUGAGUGGGAGGUUCUGCCGCCCCCCUGGUUUCCACCUUACCUGGGCAGGAAGAGUGGCCCUGUGCAGACAUAGACGUUUUGGUAGCUGCGGGUCAAGCUGCGGCUAUAUUUCUCCAGGUUGUUCCAGGCAUUCUGGUUGAGGUGGGGCACCUGGUAGGAGAGAUAGGGCUUAGCAGGACUGUGGCUGGGACCCUUCCUCCUCUAUCAGAGGGCCGCCCCAGGUCCUGAGGGGAUGGACAGGCUCAGAGAUAUCCAGUGAGACAAGCGGGGGGAAACUGAGGCUCAAGGAAUGAAAGUCACUCCCUGAAACCCAGGGCUGAUAGAGUGCUAGCCACCACCCUCUGUCCCUCCCACAGCCCAGGUGUCAAAGUCUUUUCUCAGCUCCCAAGAGUCGAAUGAAGGAAGAGCCUGUCUCCACCUUUCAGAGAGGACUGAGGCCUGUCCCCAGCCCCACCCAGGGUCUCCUGGGAAGACCAGCCCUUCCAACUACCAACCCGUUCCUUUUCCCAGUCUGAGCCACAGGAAGAGCCUAGCGGGGAAUGCCAUGAAUCGACCUCCAUCCUGAGCUCUCCAGGCCUGGGACAAUGGAAAGUGGAUAGGGGGCUGUCUUCCCAGAAGGAAGCUGGGUCAGAGGUUGGUGCCCCAUGGGCUCCACCCAGAGCCCCAUGGCAGUCUCCAUCCAUUGGUGCCAGGACCUGCUGGGAACAGGCUGAGAGGGUGGUUGGCCCAGUGCACAGUGCCUGGCACUAACAACCUGAUCGUGGGCCAGGUGUCUGCCUCGAAACUGCCUGAAGGCAGGCAGGGUAGGACAAUGUCUGGAGGCUCACGGUUUUAUAGACUAGGGGUCCCCAACCCCUGGGCUACAGACCGGUACCAGAACCGGGCCACACAGCAGGAGGUGAGCAGCAGGCGAGCAAGGGAAGCUUCAUCUGUAUUUACAGCCACCCCCCCAUUGAUCCCACAGCAGCCUGAGCUCCGCCUCCUGUCAGAUCAGUGGCGGCUGGAGAUUGUCAUAGGAGCUGGAACCCUAUGGUGAACUGCGCAUGUGAGGAGGUUGCGCGCUUCUUUUGAAAACCUAAUGCCUGAUCUGUCGUUGUUGCCCAUCACCUCCAGAUAGGACUGUCUAGUUGCAGGAAAACAAGCUCAGGGCUCCCACGGAUCCUACAUUACUGUGAGUUGUAUAUUUCACUAUAUGUUACAAUGUAAUAAUAAUAGAAAUAAAAUGUACAUAAAUGUAA